AGUGCGCCUUUCAGCCUCACCUGCAGCUGCGCCUCCUUGCACCUGCGCCUGUGCUUUUUCUCCCAGCACUGCGGACGCGACUCGAGGGUGACGCUCGCUCCGCUCGUCCCGCUCGUCAUGGCCUACCCGGGAUACGGAGGAGGGUUUGGAAAUUUUAGCAUUCAGGUGCCAGGAAUGCAGAUGGGACAGCCAGUGCCAGAAACAGGCCCAGCUAUACUCCUCGAUGGAUACUCUGGGCCAGCAUAUUCAGACACUUAUUCCUCAGCUGGUGACUCCGUGUAUACUUACUUCAGUGCUGUUGCUGGACAGGAUGGUGAAGUGGAUGCUGAAGAACUUCAGAGAUGUUUGACACAGUCUGGAAUUAAUGGAACUUACUCUCCCUUCAGUUUGGAAACCUGCAGAAUUAUGAUUGCCAUGUUGGAUAGAGAUCACACAGGAAAAAUGGGAUUUAAUGCAUUCAAAGAGCUAUGGGCAGCUCUUAAUGCCUGGAAGGAAAACUUCAUGACUGUUGAUCAAGAUGGAAGUGGCACAGUAGAACAUCAUGAGUUGCGUCAAGCCAUUGGUCUUAUGGGUUAUAGGUUGAGUCCUCAAACAUUAACUACUAUUGUUAAACGUUAUAGCAAGAAUGGCAGAAUUUUCUUUGAUGAUUAUGUUGCUUGCUGUGUGAAGCUUCGAGCAUUGACAGAUUUCUUUAGGAAAAGAGACCACUUGCAACAAGGGUCUGCGAAUUUCAUAUAUGACGAUUGUGGAGGAAUGAACGUAAUUAACUUUGAACAUCUUGAUACAGAAAGACCUGAAUCUGUGUGCAAAAGUGACUAAGUUCCCUUUAUCCCCCUGGAAUUCCCAUGAGUUGAGGAUCAUCUGAAUUUGAGUUGCAUCCAUGAACAGUUUUAUCCCUUGGUUUCUUAUUUGCGUGGAAGGCAUUUUCAUAACGAAGUACUGGUUUAGUAAAAGCAGUAAAUAGGAGUCUCCAUGCAAGAGAAAUUGGAGUUUCCUAACAUGCAUGUGAUUUAAAAAAUAAAAAUAAAAAAUAAGGUGCCGUGAGAUGCUGGCAGUUUUAACAUUUGGAACCAAAAGUUCUUAUGUAUAUUUACAUCCUAACUGCUCAGUUUUACCUUACAAGCUUCAAUUUAGGAAAAUAUACAGUACUUUUGCAUAUAAUGGUACCUUGUGAGCCCCUGAGUCAAGUAGAGAGGAUUUAAAUAGAAAAAGGAAAACAGCCAUUAAAAGCACUUACAUUGUAUGUGGAGUAAAUAGUACAAAAUGAUUAUUUCCCUGGAAGACCAGGAUCAGAAACAUGCCUAUGAAGACCCACGAUUCCUACAGUGCUUAGGGAUGAAUCUGGCAAAGAAGGAUGCCUAAUUGGAUGAACGUAAGUUUUUCUUUGCCGCAGGUGAAGCUCUAAAGAGAGAUCACUGUCUUGUUUUAAAAGUGAAGUCAAGUUGUCUUCUGAAGCUGUGUUCAGAUGCACCCCACUUGAAAGGGAUUCUUUGGAUUUAAGUUUAGAUUUUUCAAGGUCUAGAAAUUCAGGACACUGAUGGAAAAAGAACAAAACAAGUUUUUAUAAUUCACAUUGAUAGAUAGUCAUUGAAAAUUACACUAAUAAAAACUUAAGCAUUUUCUUUCCUCAUUAAUCUAUAUUUGAUUAGUGAUAUUAGCCAACAUUUCCCUCCUAAAAUGAGUCAGGACGUCGGAGAUUGGUUAUCAGUACAGAUAAUCCUAAACAACCAUUCCAAGAACUUUUAUUUAACCCUGGAACCAGAUUUUAAAAAUCAGAUUUAAAAAAAUAUAUAUUAUUUUACAUUGAGUUUUCCAGAUGAAUUAAAUUCGAAAUUUAAGACAAAUUGGGAUGAGGAAUGGGAUCACUUGAUGAAUAAGAGGGUAUAAGGAGGAAAGAAAAGAUGGGAAGAUGGGAAGUAAAAUCCGUCAUCCCUAGUCAGAUAAUAUUACCUAAAUCCACUGAAAACAAAGAACAAAAUAGAUGGUUUUACAUGUUUCCCAGUCAUUCAAAACUAGUUAAAUUAAUUUCUACUUUCAGAUUUUUAGAAGUAUUGCGUUAUUUUCCUUCUGACACAUUACCUUCUCUUAUUAGUGUAAUUUCAUUUUCCAGAACGUCUUAAAUUAAAUUCCCGAACAUCUAAAAAAGUUUUAUGAGAUUGUUCUACAAAUCUUUAUUUAAAUCAUUGUUCUUAGGUCCAAUUUCACCAUAAUGUUUAACUAAUUAAGACUAAUUCCCAAAAUAGAAUUGCAAGGAAAGCUAGACUACUUACAUUAACAUAAUUCAAAAGGACCCCUUUGAGGGCUUCAGAAGCAGGAUAAAGGACUCUUUAAAUUGCUUCUCUUACCAUGUUUAUCAUCCAAGUAAAAAAAUUUAGAGAUCUCUGGUGAUGGGUGGGGUACAGACAAGAUUACUAGUCUGAUGGCAUUUGAACCUCAGGUCUAAUCUGGCCAGCCUACUAUUUCUCCUCCCCUUCCUUCCUGAGACCUCUCCCAGCCUUUGGCACUGUAGAAAAUUACAGAUUUUUCUUUGAAGCUCUUUUGGGACCCAGAUUUUUCCUUAAAGCCCUUUUAAGAGCCAGGAAGACUAUUCCUUAGAUUUCAAAGCUCUACCACAUGUAAAUUUAAGCAGGUUGAUUCUGGAAGAAAGGUUUUCCUUUUAAAAAAAAUGCUAAUGUUUAAAAUUAUUAUUCUAGCUUCAUUGUUCUCAAACUUUAAAUGAACAUAAAAAUCAGCGUGGGCUUGUUUAAAAUGCAGAUUACAGGGCCCAUUUCCAGAAAUUCUAUUUGAGUAGAAACAGAGAUAGGGACAGAAAUCUGCCUUUUCCACAGCACCCCAAGUGAUUCUGAUUAGGUGACCCCUGGAAACACACUGUGAGAGACACUCUUGGUUGGAUGGUAUCCACACUUACUUGUGAGGAAGGGCUGAAACUUCGGUCAGUUUUGAUGGAUGCUUCCGGUUGACUGGUUCUCAUCAGCUGGAUGAUGGGUCUCUGAUAUUCUGAUCCUGCUGUUACCAUACUGUAGGCUGGGGGGACCACAGUGGUUUGUUUCUGCAGCAACUGUAAGAUGGUCUGGAUGUCAGUGGUCAUUUGGGAUUCAAGCCUACAGAACAGACAGAAGUAGGAAAAGACAGUCUAAAAUAGUCCAGAAUUUCAGGAGCAUUUAAAAAAAUUUCAGCACUACCAAGAAACAGAAUUAUGGCCUUGCUUUAAACAAGAAGGACAGGAGAGGGAGCACAGAGAUUCUUUCCUGACGGAUACUUACUGUGUAUGUCUCACUAAUUAUUCUGAUAAAGACUAUUGCUUUCCUGUUCAUAUUAAGAGUUAACAGAAAAUCAAAUGAACAAAAUAGACUACAUGUUUACUAACCUUCAUUGAUUUCAAAAUGUAAAACACACUGACAAUUUAUUUUUAAUCAGUAAUUGUCUUUGCUUUUUAAUUAGGUUUUACUCAGUUUCUUGUGAACAUUUUAUUUGCUCUUAAAAAAUAGAUUGGUAGCACAUUUCUUUCAUAACUGUAGCAUCCCAGGAUAAUUUCUUAUGUGUUUUUACAUUUAUAUUAACACUUUUUAACCUUACCUCUGUCCUAUUCAUAUUAAGUAUUGUAUAUUAUUCAUUGUAUUCUUUCUUUAAUGUUUAAUGCUGUUAAAUGUUAAAUUCUUUUUCCCUCUUAAUAUGUCAUGGCCUUUGGUAUGUAAGAAGCAGACCAAACUUGACUUCACUUGCUUCUAAUGACCCAUCUGGCCUGCAAAAUACCAGUUUAUUUUUUCCCUAAAGCUCACAAGUAGCCAACUGGCCUGUUAAUUUCAUUCUCAUUUUAAAUUAAAAUUUAAGGGAAAAUAGCAAAAUAUAAUUGGUCAGAUUCCCCUCCUUUGCAUGUGUUAACAACAGCAUUAAAUACAGAGGAAAUUUUGUGGACAUAAGAACAGAAAAUUUGGACCAUAUGCCUCUUUAGAAAAUUCUUCUAACUCUUCACUUAUUUGCGCUGACUGUUUUGCCUCUGAAUAAAAAAUGGAAAUAAAACAAAAAAAGGAAAAUCAUAGGAUUAAUUUUGCCCAAUUAAAUUCAUGCUAUAUUUGUAGAAUUCAAAGUAGAAAUUAGCUUUUGAUUUGAUAGAGAACAUAAUAAACCUGGAAAACAUGAGAAAAUAUCUUCUUUUUUUUUUAGUUUUUGAUAUUAACACUCCAAAUCUUCCUUCUAAGAAUCACAAUAACACAUUAUUCUUGCAGUUUUUCUAUAGUUAGUAAAUAUAGCCAUAUAGCUUUGUGUCUUCUAAACCAAUAGCUAUGAAUGAUACAUGACUUUGCAAAUGUCAUUUUUGCAAAUGUCAAAACCACUCUGAAAAGGGAAAAAUUGAGUUAUCAACUGGUUUAUUUAUCUACUCUUGAUACCUGAAGGUCUGAUCUAAUUUUUAUGCUUCCAACUAAACUAAGCAGACCCAUUAUUUCACUGUUAUGUGUUAUACAUAUUUUUCUUUCAUUUCACUCUUCAAGUCCCAGCUUAUAUGUUAUCUGUAUCCCAAAAUCUUUCCUUAUUUACCCCAUUCAGAAUUACUUUCUCCUCUGAGCCUCCAAAGAAAAUUAUACAUUCAGAUUUAUCAUAAAUAUUUCUGUACAAAUGUAUUCCAUUACUAACAGCAUUCAGUUGUGAGUGGCUUACAACAAUGUUUAUUACAUUGAAUGUAAAAGGAUUUGGGGGGAAAGACUGGAAGAAGAACUGCAUCAACAAGGGAGAUUCAAGAUCCAAAAAUGAGUCAAAAAUUAUCGUGAUGUUUUUGUCAUAUAAAUCCUUUGCCAAACAGCAGCUGUCUCUGAGAAAUAAAAUCUCUUUAUCAUGGA